AAGAGCCCUGCUCCUGGAGCUGAGAACUGCAGCGCGGAGGCUUCGGAGCGAGCCGGGGCAGUCGGGGUCGAGGCAGCCCCUCCUGACUGUGACUUUGGACACCUCGCUGAAUCUCUGCUUCCUCCCCUGCAAAAAUGAAAAUUCAUUCAAUGGAUGAAGUUAAGAAGUGCCAAGGGUGAGGAUCUCCUUUAGAAGAGGAGAAGCCUUGCAUCAACCUCUUGGGCCUCAGCCAAGAUGUCUGAGAUACCGUCCACUAUAGUCUCCAAGAACAUGACCAAUGACAAGAACAGCCUGGAAUCCAUGAACAUCAGCUCUUCUUCAAGCACUGAAGAGAACCCAAAGAAACAGGCAAGAAAAAACGAAGAACAUGGUCCUGACCCUUCAGCGAACCCUUUCCACUUAUCUGGGGAUGUGGAUUUCUUCUUGCUCAGAGAUCAGGAGCGGAAUAAGGCUCUCUCCGAACGGCAGCAGCAGAAGACGAUGCGGGUGCACCAGAAGAUGACCUACUCCUCGAAAGUGUCGGCUAAGCACACCAGCCUGCGGCGGCAGCUGCAGCUGGAGGACAAGCAGGAGGACCUGGAGGCGCGCGCCGAGGCCGAGCAUCAGCGCGCCUUCCGCGACUACACGACCUGGAAGCUCACCUUGACCAAAGAAAAGAAUGUGGAGCCUGAGAACAUGAGUGGCUACAUUAAGCAGAAGCGGCAAAUGUUCCUCCUCCAGUAUGCCCUGGAUGUCAAGCGGAGAGAGAUCCAGCGGCUGGAGACGCUGGCGACCAAAGAGGAGGCCAGGCUGGAGCGGGCCGAGAAAUCCCUGGAGAAGGACGCCGCCUUGUUCGACGAGUUCGUCAGGGAGAAUGACUGCAGCUCCGUGCAGGCCAUGAGAGCGGCUGAGAAGGAGACCAAAGCCAAGAUAGAGAAGAUCCUUGAGAUCCGGGACCUCACCACCCAGAUUGUUAAUAUCAAAAGUGAGAUCUCCAGAUUUGAAGACACUCUGAAGCAUUACAAGGUCUAUAAGGAUUUCCUAUACAAGCUGUCGCCCAAGGAGUGGCUUGAAGAACAGGAAAAGAAACACUCGUUUCUCAAAAAGGCCAAGGAGGUCUCCGAGGCUUCCAAAGAGAGCAGUGUUAACUCCACACCAGGGGACAAAGGACCAGGGAUCAAGGGCAAGGCGAGCUCCAUGUGGGCCAAAGAGGGUCAGGGUACAAAGAAGCCCUGGAGGUUUCUGCAGACGAUGCGGCUGGGGCGGAGCCCGUCUUACCUGAGCAGCCCCCAGCAAGGCAGCCAGCCCAGCGAGUCCAGCGGUGGCGACUCCAGAGGUGUGGCCACGCCUUGUGGUGAAGACCAGCCACCACUGGGGCAUGCUGCUGCGCCACGCACAGGCUGCUGUUAACGUUGCCCACCAUGACGCCCUGCUGGUGGGGGGACAUUUCCAGUUCUGCGUUGAGGAGCAGAGGUUCUAAUGUAUGCAGUGCAGCCUGCUCCGCCUAGGGCUCCCUCAGCCAUGGACUGCCCCCUACCAGACAGGCCCUCACUUGGGAGACUUGAGAACAGAGUCGGGGAUCACACUGUCCUGGGUUUCAAUCCUGGCCCCUCCAUCUAUUUGCCAGGUGACCAGGGCCACUGAGUAUAGCUGGGCAGGUUGUGAGCUAUAUAAGGCACUCACUCAGCCAAGAGGGAACAUGGGGGCUGAAGUCCAGCCCAUGCCCACCAACCGCCAGGUCAGGCUCCCUGACCCAGGCUACAUCCAUCUGGAGGGUGGAUUAUCAGAAAGGCAUCGUAUGGGCCAGCAGCGCCCUGCAGGCAGCCGGCUCUCUCAUCUGUAAAAUGGGCAUCGGUGUGCAGUGUGAGGCGUGGGUCUGGCGAGUGCUGUAGUUGUUAUCACAGCCUCUCCUGGGAAGCCCUCCUGGAUCUGCUGUCAGAGUCCCACAGGACCUUGCCCUGAUGCCUCUCUGCUUCUGGGGAUCAGGGGCUGGCAUCUCCAAGCCCAAGCUUAGGUCCCUGAGGUGCCUGGGGCAAGCCAGCGCAGCCCCCCCCACCUCAGUCAGCAGGACCUGCAGAUCCUAGGUGAGGCCCAGGGUGGAGCAGGCUGGGAGGGCAGGUUUGGAAGUCAGUGCAGGUGAGGUCCCCAUCGAGUGGGGCCUUCUGGGGCCCACACUGAGUGCUUAAAGCUCACACAGCUUGUUCCCAGCCCCUCUCCACUGGUCCAGGACAGACCUUGCCCCUGGGCACUCAGGAUCACCUGGAGGCAGCCCUGAGAGUCCCUCUAUUGCUGUGAGUGGGACCCCCAGGACAGGGGCCAAGACUGACCCUAGAUGGGGGAGGCAGGGCAGGAAAGGCCUCAAAGGUGGCACUCAGUAAACAAGGGUGAGGGAGGAGGGGCAGCCCCAG